AGGUCUCCAUGGAGGCGGCUUCUCCUAGCAACUCGACGGGCGUUGAGCGGAGCCGCUGACCUGAUGGACGCCGACAGCCUCCUGCUGUCUCUGGAGCUGGCGUCCGGCAGUGGGCAGGGCCUCAGCCCGGACCGUCGGGCCUCGCUGCUCACGUCUCUUAUGCUGGUUAAGCGCGACUACCGCUAUGAUCGGGUUCUCUUCUGGGGCCGCAUCCUUGGCCUCGUCGCCGAUUACUACAUCGCGCAGGGCCUGAGUGAGGACCAGCUCGCACCGCGCAAGACGCUCUAUAGCCUGAACUGCACAGAGUGGAGCCUCUUGCCCCCUGCCACAGAGGAGAUGGUGGCGCAGUCGUCUGUGGUGAAGGGCCGCUUCAUGGGGGACCCAUCAUACGAAUAUGAACACACUGAGCUGCAGAAGGUGAAUGAAGGUGAAAAAGUCUUUGAAGAAGAAAUAGUGGUCCAGAUCAAGGAAGAGACCCGCUUGGUGUCUGUCAUUGACCAGAUUGACAAGGCUGUGGCCAUCAUCCCCCGAGGCGCCCUCUUCAAGACCCCUUUUGGACCCACCCAUGUCAAUCGGACCUUUGAAGGACUGUCCUUGUCUGAGGCCAAGAAGCUCAGCUCCUACUUCCAUUUCAGGGAGCCUGUUGAGCUAAAGAAUAAGACCUUGCUUGAGAAGGCUGACCUGGACCCCUCCCUGGAUUUCAUGGACUCCUUGGAGCAUGACAUUCCCAAAGGGUCUGAGGCAGUUGUUCAGGGUGACUUCACGUGGCUUCUGAGCAGGUGUGGUUUUGGUUGGCCCUGUUCCUGGGACUCCUGCUCUGUGUCCAUGAGGGUCCUGGAGCAUCCAGAUGGAGAGGGGCAAUGCCCUGGUGGUGCUGCGCAGCCUGCUCUGGCCGGGCCUCACCUUCUACCAUGCUCCCCGCACCAAGAACUAUGGCUACGUCUACGUGGGCACUGGCGAGAAGAACAUGGACUUGCCCUUCAUGCUAUAGAAUGGGAGCCAGCCUGGAUGUUUUUAAACAGAGUCUAAACAUGAUUUUCUUAAGCUUCAGUGAACUUGGCCUGCCUGUUCUGUCCUAUCUUCUUAACUCCACCUCCGUCUGGUUCCAGAUUCUGAAAGGCCCACUGAGCCAGGGAGCUCAUUUCUAAACCAAGUGGCAGAGGGGUUGGAAUGUGCUAAUGAAAGAGAUUCUAGACAACGAUGGGUGGAAAUGGCUGUGGGAGAAGGUGACAACCAGGGCCCCUUUGAGGAACGCAGUUUCUUGGAUUCACACGAGAGCGGCAAGUGUGUCAGGCAGCCCACCUUGGCUCCCUGCAGCUCUCCCACAGUAAGGAGCUCACAGCUGUCAUGAAGAGGAUGGGACCUGUUUGGCCCAUGAAUUCAAUUGACUCAUUGGCCCCAUCACAAGAGAUCAGUGACUCAAUGCUCAGCACCCAGCUGGCAAUGUGCCCAGGACCCCCUGCACUUCCCAAGCAGUGAGCGCACACCCAAUGGGUAAGCCCAUGAACCCAGUUUAUGACACUGCGUUGGGCAAAACUCCUGUCCCCAGCACUGAGCAUGGCCUAAGCCCCAUAGCAGCUGGCAAGGGACCCAACUGCCCUGCCUGCCUCUAGCUCCCAGCAUUGCUACUGUGCAGGCCAAGGGUACUGAAGUUAGUCCCACUGUCCCCUGUCCAUGCAUGUUGGAGGGACCAGGCCAUCGUGGUGGGGUGGGACAGGAGUAUAGUUGUGGCCAAGGGCUUGUGAGUGGGCCUCCUACUCCCCAGCACAGGUGCAGGAGGAACUCUGGAAGCACUGCUCUCUGUCAGUGAUACAGCUUCCAAGGUGUUCUUGAGUAGCAGACAUUGUCCCUCAGAAGGGGUGACCCCACGGGCAUGCGCACCCUGUUCCAGCGGGGGCCUUUUUUGUAGAUGGGCUUGACGGAGCCAGGAGCCCAGCGCGUCAGGUACCUGUGGAGGGAGAACAAAGAGGUGCCUGUGAGGGCUGGGGGCCCAAGCUGGACGUGGGAGAGUGGAGCACUACCUCCUCAGGCCAGGCCACGGUUGGGCAAGCAAAUCCUUUCACCAGUUUCCCUUUCCUGAAGUGCAGGGAUUUUCCUGGGAGUAACUGCUGAGCGUCCUGUAAACAGAUGGGCUGGGCUCUUGCUGCCGCAAGCCUGUGUGGCCAGGUUCAGGCAGCCCAGGGCCACAAGCUCCCUUGAUCUUUGUAAAUGUCAAUGUUGGUGUGUGUUUGCUGAGGAAAAGGUGGCGAAGAGGCUGCCUGAAGAGCAGAUCAUUCCUCUCUGGCCUCAGCCAUGGGGCGAGAAGAGCUGAUGUAAGGCUCUGGAGGAACCCAUUGCUCUUCCCCAUUUGGCUCACUCAGCUACCCCAACCUUCAGGGAACUCCCCAGGGUACUAUAACUGGUAUAAGACCCCUGCCCCUCACCCAACCUGUGAUGGGAAUCAAGGGGUAAGGGCCCGUGGGCGCAGCCCUAGCCUAGGAAGGUUCCUGUAAAUAGGAGGGGGGUGGGGAAAGAUGGCUGCCGCCCAUGGACCUUUGGCCUCCUUUGGGGAUGGCCAGGGCCCUGAUAGUUCCCAGAAAAGUGGCUCAUGCCGGCUAGGAUUGGGUUUUACUCUGUCCAGAAUAAAACUUGGAUCCUGUCCA